AGUCCCUGGGCUGCAGCCGCUGCUACACAUACUCACAACGCUGCCGCCGCGCUCCGUGGGCAACUCCUACUACUGCUGGGCUGGGCUGGGCUGGGCUGGGCUGCGCCGGAGCUCGCCUGCACAGAUCAGCUCCGGAGAGGGGAAAACCACGCUCCUCGGACCAAGCCUCGGGAGCUAAGCCAGAUCUGCCAGUGAGCCUCAGGCUUUAGGAACUGAAGAGUGGUUCUUUUGAAUGACUUGCAAGAACAAUUUUAAGGGUAGAAGUAGCCCCUGCAUUUUGAUUUUGCUGGAUCUGACAUAUGGUUCUGAUGAGCAUUGGGAUGGAUGUAGGAAGGCACACCACAGACCUGGCCAGGAGAAAUGAUGGGAUGGUUCUCAGAGCUCUUCCCUUGCUUCCUCAUCCCUGUUUAAUAAAAAGUGAAAGAUACAAGCAAGUAACAUGAAACAAAGCUAAAAAAGAUCACUUAUUAAAGAAAGAAAGAGGAAACUGUUAAAUAACAGCUCCAGCAAAAGCCCAAUGGAACAAACAAACAGCCACAAAGGACCAGGGAAGGCUCUUUGUCUGAAUUAAAAAUAACUAAAAAUGGUACAAUGUGCACUGAACGCAAAUGUGCAACUCAUUGCAGAGCCCUCGAACUCUGUAACGUUCCAACCUCUGAGAUGAGGAAUGUCUCUGCCAUCCAUAGGGAAGAGCUUCCCGGCCAACUGCUCCUGGAACCAAGGCACUGUCCCCUUUCUUUGACAGCUAGCUACAGCACUUGGGUAUUGUCAAUUCUCCCUUCAGUGCUCCUACUGCAAUACCAUGAGGAUUUGGUGGAAAUCAAAUGCUGAGGUAAUCCAGACCACUCAUUAAUAAAGACCAUAAGAUUCUGGUGUAUUUCCCUUCAGCAGCAGUGAGGAAAGAUGGAAAAAGUGGAAAGAAAGAGCAGCUGUGAGAAGAUCUCUGUAUCUGAUAGUGCCUUGUUGAGCUUUCUGGGACCCCCAUCUCUACUCUGGAAUUGACCUGAUCUUCAAGGACCUAUGUCCUGGUGUAUGAUUCUCUCCCUUUUAACACCACCCUGUCUCUACAGCAUAUUUCUUGUCCUGACCCCUUUCUGACAAACAGUUUGCUCUAAGGCUUGUUUGGAGAACUUGAUCCUUUCCCCUCUCCCUGCCUGUUUCAGCCCCCGCCCCUACCUCCAUCAGCUCUUGACUGGCUUUGCCUCCACCAGGUUCCAGCCACUCUCUAACUGAUGCCACAGUCUCUGAGCCAGCCCUACUCCCUUGAGGGUUAGGCCAUCCCUAGCUGGGAUGGAACUGAAGUAAUAAUAGUUCCGACAUUAAACAGAAUUAGGACUUGUGUUCAAAAUUGAGGAUAGAGAAAGGAAAAUAAACUUUUUAAAGUAUGGUAAAAUACCUGUAGCAUAAAACUUACCAUCAUAACCAUUUUUAAGACUACAGUUCAGUGGCAUUAAAUGCAUUCACAUUGUUGUUCAACCAUGAUCAUCAUCCAUCUACAGAGCUCUUCGUCUGGCAACACUGAAAAUCCAACACAGUGAAACCCCCAUCUCUAUCAAAAAAUUUUUAAAAAUUUAAAACCUGACACUCUGUUUUAAAUAAACAAUAGCUCCCUAUUCUGCCCUCCCCCCAGUCCCUGGCAGUCAGCAUUCUGCUUUCUGUCUCUAUGAAUUUGACUACAUACAUAUAAGUGGAAUCACACAGUAUUUGUAUUUUUAUGACUGGCUUAUUUCACUUAGCAUAACGUCUUUAAAGUUCAUCCACAUGGUAGCAUGUGUCAGAAUUUCCAUUCUUUUCACAGUGCAAUAAUAUUCCAUUGGAAGUAUUUGUCAUGUUUUGUUUCCCCAUUCACCCAUCAAUGGACACUUGGGUUGCUUCCACCUUUUACCUAAUGUAAAUAAUGCUGCUAUGAACACCAGUGUACAAAUAUGUCUUCAAGACCCUGAUUUUAAUUCUUUCAUGUAUAUACUCAGAAAUGAAAUUGUUGGAUCAUAUGAUAGUUGUAUUUUUAAUUUUUUAAGGAAGCAUCAUACUGUUUUCCAUGGCAGCUGAACCAUUUUACAUUCCCCCCAACAGUACCCAAGGGCUCCAAUUUCUCCAUAUCCUCACCAGUACUUGUUAUUUUCUGUUUUUUAAAUUCUAAUUCUGAAAGGUGUGAGGUGAUAGCUCAUUGCCAUUUUUAUUUGCAUUUCCCUAAUGAUUAGUGACUUGGAGCAUUUUUAUAUACUUAUUGAAAAAGUUAAGAACAUGAAAUCUCAUACAAAUAUGUAACAAGCACAUGUAAAAGAUUUGAUUAACUCACUGAAGGAAACACUGAGUGAAAAAACCUGGUUUCAGGAAUACACGAGACUGAAUUAUAUAUAAUCAAUGAAAGAAGAAAUGUGGAAAUGAGAUUGCCAAGUUAUAUUCAACACUGGUUAAUGUCCCACAGGGCAAUAAAACCAUAAGCUUUGGGGUUAUUUUUUCAUUCAAAUAAGUGUCCUCCUACAGUGUCAGAUGAACCUAGGAUCUAGUAUGACAUUGAAGGGCACACAGUAAUCUUUCUGCCUUCUUUCUGAGCUUUGGAACAUUUUUCUUAACAGACUCAAUACUUUUACUCCCAGAAACCAGUUCUGUGUCUUCUUUCCAUGUUCUCUGCAAGAGGGUAGAAAUGGGCCUGGGGCAGAGCAGAGAGAAACUUUGCUUUCCUAAAGUUCUUUCCAGCUGGCCUUAGUGAGAUUUUGGAUCUAUUGGUCGUCUAAUUGCCAGAAAGAGUAGCUCAACAGUCAUGAUUGAAUAAAAGUAAUGGUGUAAAUGUAUCCAUCCUUUAUAUGCUUUCAUCAGCUGACUUUGGGUUUUGUUUAUUUAGGUUAGAUAUUCAGUCUAUGCAUGCAAAGCUCAAAUGUGGAGAAUUUGAGGAUGAUACCAGUGUGUUCCCACACCCUGCCAUAUUGACCAUCUAAAAUAUUUGAGAAUGCUUAGGAUUUGCUAUCUAAGGAUGAUACUGUGAAGUGUUCAGGAAUGAAGUCUCGUGAUGUCUGCUACCUAGUUUCAAAUGGCAGGAGAGACAGAGGGAUGGGGAAGCAAAAGUGACCAUUGUUAACUCUAGGUGGUUGGUCAUAAAAUUGCUGUUAUGUAUGUGAAAACGGCCAAAUAUACCAUAGACCCCAGAUUAGGAUCAGUCUGGUGCCUCUGAAAAUGUGAAUUGAGAAGAACUGAAAGAAAAUCUUUCCCUGGGGAGACUGCAGCCGAAACACCCUUCUGACGAAUGUGCUGACCUAAUCUAAGCCUCAAUUUCCUUCAACAAGGGAUGCAUCGCUCACUUCCCUUGAGUUGUGAGAAUGAAACAAGAUAAUGCGUUAAAGCCCUUGGCCCAGUUCCUGGCAUGUGGCGAGCUCUUGGUCCAUAAGCAAAUCUUCGUAUUAGUUGUUUCUGAAAGAUCUAUCCAGCACUCCGAUGGCCAGCAACAACACCGCCAGCAUAGCACAAGCCAGGAAGCUGGUAGAGCAGCUUAAGAUGGAAGCCAAUAUCGACAGGAUAAAGGUGUCCAAGGCAGCUGCAGAUUUGAUGGCCUACUGUGAAGCACAUGCCAAGGAAGACCCCCUCCUGACCCCUGUUCCGGCUUCAGAAAACCCGUUUAGGGAGAAGAAGUUUUUCUGUGCCAUCCUUUAAGUCUUUGAGAGGGGCCUGAAGAGCCUCCGGGCUCCUGGGACAUUGAUGUAGAGUUUUUAGUGAAGUGGGCACCUUUCUAGUCCACGGCAUUUGAAGAGAGCGAGGAGAACCAUUCUGGAAACUCUAGGCUAUGCAUGUUUAAAGAUCUGGUCCCCUUUAUGAGAAUGCAAGCCGAUCCACAUCCUGACUUAAGAGAUCUGAUUCUGACGAACUGCCUGGAGGAGGGGAAUAUAUAAAAAUAAAAUUGGUGUCACUUCUUUUCUGCUAUCCCCCAGCCCCCCCCCCAAAAUCCUCAUGUUUCUGCUUCAUAUUUUGAAAAAUAACAAUUAAAACAGACAGCUGUACUGAGGUAAGAUAUGUGUGACCUUCUUGGAAUGAAUAUUGUCUUUAGAAUACCCUUUGAUAAGCUGAGCUGUCCCGUGUAGAUGCAAUUCGGUUUAAUGGCAUUGAUGUAUAGUCACUGUGCCUUUCUUUUUCUUUCUUCCUUCUCCUCUACCCCUCCUUCCACCCCUCCCCAUUAGAGUAGUGUGGAGAUAAGGCUGGACUGGUCUAUCAGAUUGAACUCCAAGAAUGAUCACACAAAAUGUUUAGGGAGAUGUUCCCCGUGGUGUAUCCUCAUGGUAACAACGACAAAAAAUGCCGGUUGUCUGUGUUCUCUUUUCACUAUUCCUAACAUGUGUACAUGAUAGCUUUGAUUCUGCAAGUAAAAGUAAAUCCUGUGUUGUGACUGGUGCUUUCAUAUAUUUGUGACAAUUUUUGAGUAAUAUUGCAUGAAAAUGUCCCUAUGUUACAUCCAUUCAGAAGUUUUGUUGUUUUACUCUAAAGCUGGGAAAGGAAAUGAGAGGGAAAAGACCCCGGAGAGGGAAGAAAAUCUCAGUAUUUUGAAAAUUGAGAUUACUUCAGAGCCUUAGCCACACCUAAAAUACCUCCUAGUUAAUAGUGGUAUAAAUGCCUCUUCAAUACGUUUUCCAGAAUCCAAAGCAUUUUGGUUUAUCCAGGACCCAGGGCAGCACAGCUGUCACCAAGCAGGAGAGUUAAGGAUUCACCAUGAGCUGGGAAAUGCUUUUGCCAUGAGUAUGAGCAAAUUCCCUCUUUCCCUGAAUCAUGGACAUUCUAGAUUAAAAGAACAUUUUUUUGUGCUCUUAACAAGAAAACCAUGGCCCUCCUUUGUUCAAGUAUCAGAAGAAAUAAACCCACAGCUCCAGAGAAGGUGACCAUUCUCAGAACUCCAGCUAUUCACUCUCCAGGGAGAAGGACCUCAAAUCGCCACUCUUUGGGCGGCAGGUGCGGUCCCCACGGCCGGCUCUACGAGGAAGAGUUCUGGCUCUUUUGUCCACUGAGAUGGUCUUGGUUUUUCACUUAACAAAUUUUUUAAUGGAAUCUUUGUUUUUGUUCUCCAUCUUGUUUGUUAGAGUCUCUCGGCCUUUAUUUACAAAUUCCUUGCAACUAGAGCGCUCCUUCCCCAAGAUAUGGUAGUGAGAGUAAUUUUUCAUUGUAGCUGUAGUCUCCAUCAGUAACAGCAGGCCCUGGAAGACUUGAUCACCUUUUUCUGUGUCAUUUUCAGUCAAAGAGGGCCUCUCUUACAUCUUGUUUGCUUUCAAAUCCCCAAAUAUCAUCUCCAUCUCCCAAUUAAUUUUAUUGUCUCUUUCCUCUCUAUUCGCUUUCUCCUGUUUUUUUUUUAAAAAAAAAGCAUGAAAAAGGAAGAGAAAAAGUUUGAUAUGCCAAGGACAGAUUUUGAAACAGACUUGGUAAAUGUUUUCCUUAGCUCCUUCAUGGGCAUGCUGGUGAAAGAAUAAAUACAUCCAAUUAAAGCUCAUGCUGGGGUCGGGGAGAAGAGGAUACUGAAACAUUUGUGAAAUGUAUGAAUGCACUUCUGUAACCAGAUACUUCUGUUCUUCUGUUCAAAUUGUGGGGUUUUUGUUACAGUUAGGACGCCCAUGAAGAUUUAGGGGUGAAAAAAACAGCAGAGUAUUUAUUAAACUACAGCAUUGUACAAUUAGCUUAGUAACACUAUGGAAUAAGCUAAAACAUAUCACAGUUUUUACAUGGGCCAAAACAUGAAUUGAGUAUGUGGUCACAUGAAAACACGGAUGAAUGAAUAAAACACUCUUUGGUGGUGACUGAGGCAUCAUUAGAAGGCCCAGACGAUUUCCACUAUUCACAGCAUUUCCUUUUCUCAGAAGGACUCUUUAUAUUUCCAUGUAAAUCUAGAUCUUUGGAGCAAUUAAGAUGGAAUUACAAUUUCUAGGGAGCAUUUUAAGGAAAAUGUUUUGGCUUUUUCAUAAUUUUAUGUCUUACAGUAUGGAAUUAUAAUACGAAAAUCUUUAUAUGAGUUUUGGCUUCUUGGUAUUUGUACUUAUUCAGGGGAAAAAGUCUUUCGAUUACUUAUGCCUCUAUAGAGCUUAAUUUCUUGAGAAAUUCAACAGUCAUUUUCACCAGCAUAAUUUUAUCUUAAGGAAUAACUAAUAGGAAAAGUCAGCUUAAUUAUUUAAGGCCCUAGUUUCUACAUAUAAUAUAUUCGAUAGAAAUGAAAAUCUGCCGUGGAAUUAACUAAUAAGUAGUAACAAUAAACUUCAUAUUUAGAAUGCAAAGUCUAUAAAGAAUAAUUUUACAUGAUCCUCAAUAUCAACUCCAGUUUAAAAAGUGUUAUUUUUAAAACAUUUGAAACCAAGUACUGUUUAAUUUCAAUCAGAAGAUGCAAAUACAUACUUUGAUCUAUGUUUGAUUUUGCUAAUAAUAUUUGAAGGAGAUUGCCUACCAAGGACAAAACAAUAAAUUUAAAAAUCAAACGAUUUCUCCAUACGCUCAUAGUCACAUAUGGAAUUUUGAGAAAAUAAAGCAUGCUGUCUUUAGGAAUUUUUAUACUUCUUUGUCUUUCUUCCUUAAUAUUUGCUUCUAGCUGCUCUUGGCAAUGAUGAAUUGUUAUGUAUGCAUUAAUGUUUUGCAGCCCAAAAGUUGUUCACAUUUUUCCUAUAUAAGAUCUGUGGAGUGUGUGUUUCAAAGAGAGAACUACAGAAAUGUUAAAGCAGGAAAACCUGAAUGUGAUGUGCACAUUUUCAUCCCACAUGGACAAUGUAUGUGUUUUAAUAAAUGGAAUUUUCAGAUUCA